ACUUGUCCGUCACGUGCGGCCGCCCGGCCUCUCGGCCUUGCCGCGCGCCUGGCGGGGUUGGGGGGGCGGGGACCAAGAUCUGCUGCGCCUGCGUUGUGGGCGUUCUCGGGGAGCUGCUGCCGUAGCUGCCGCCGCCGCUACCACCGCGUUCGGGUGUAGAAUUUGGAAUCCCUGCGCCGCGUUAACAAUGAAGCAGAGUUCGAACGUGCCGGCUUUCCUCAGCAAGCUGUGGACGCUUGUGGAGGAAACCCACACUAACGAGUUCAUCACCUGGAGCCAGAAUGGCCAAAGUUUUCUGGUCUUGGAUGAGCAACGAUUUGCAAAAGAAAUUCUUCCCAAAUAUUUCAAGCACAAUAAUAUGGCAAGCUUUGUGAGGCAACUGAAUAUGUAUGGUUUCCGUAAAGUAGUACAUAUCGACUCUGGAAUUGUAAAGCAAGAAAGAGAUGGUCCUGUAGAAUUUCAGCAUCCUUACUUCAAACAAGGACAGGAUGACUUGUUGGAGAACAUUAAAAGGAAGGUUUCAUCUUCAAAACCAGAAGAAAAUAAAAUUCGUCAGGAAGAUUUAACAAAAAUUAUAAGUAGUGCUCAGAAGGUUCAGAUAAAACAGGAAACUAUUGAGUCCAGGCUUUCUGAAUUAAAAAGUGAGAAUGAGUCCCUUUGGAAGGAGGUGUCAGAAUUACGAGCAAAGCAUGCACAACAGCAACAAGUUAUUCGAAAGAUUGUCCAGUUUAUUGUUACAUUGGUUCAAAAUAACCAACUUGUGAGUUUAAAACGUAAAAGGCCUCUACUUCUAAACACUAAUGGAGCCCAAAAGAAGAACCUGUUUCAGCACAUAGUCAAAGAACCAACUGAUAAUCAUCAUCAUAAAGUUCCACACAGUAGGACUGAAGGUUUAAAGCCAAGGGAGAGGAUUUCAGAUGACAUCAUUAUUUAUGAUGUUACUGAUGAUAAUGCAGAUGAAGAAAAUAUCCCAGUUAUUCCAGAAACUAAUGAGGAUGUUAUAUCUGAUCCCUCCAACUGUAGCCAGUACCCUGAUAUUGUCAUCGUUGAAGAUGACAAUGAAGAUGAGUAUGCACCUGUCAUUCAGAGUGGAGAGCAGAAUGAACCAGCCAGAGAAUCCCUAAGUUCAGGCAGUGAUGGCAGCAGCCCUCUCAUGUCUAGUGCUGUCCAGCUAAAUGGCUCAUCCAGUCUGACCUCAGAAGAUCCAGUGACCAUGAUGGAUUCCAUUUUGAAUGAUAACAUCAAUCUUUUGGGAAAGGUUGAGCUGUUGGAUUAUCUUGACAGUAUUGACUGCAGUUUAGAGGACUUCCAGGCCAUGCUAUCAGGAAGACAAUUUAGCAUAGACCCAGAUCUCCUGGUUGAUUCUGAGAAUAAAGGAUUAGAAACUACCAAGAACAAUGUAGUUCAGCCAGUUUCGGAAGAGGGAAGAAAAUCUAAAUCCAAACCAGAUAAGCAGCUUAUCCAGUAUACCGCCUUUCCACUUCUUGCAUUCCUCGAUGGGAACCCUGCUUCUUCUGUUGAACAGGCGAGUACAACAGCAUCAUCAGAAGUUUUGUCCUCUGUAGAUAAACCCAUAGAAGUUGAUGAGCUUCUGGAUAGCAGCCUAGACCCAGAACCAACCCAAAGUAAGCUUGUUCGCCUGGAGCCAUUGACUGAAGCUGAAGCUAGUGAAGCUACACUGUUUUAUUUAUGUGAACUUGCUCCUGCACCUCUGGAUAGUGAUAUGCCACUUUUAGAUAGCUAAAUCCCCAGGAAGUGGACUUUACAUGUAUAUAUUCAUCAAAAUGAUGAACUAUUUAUUUUAAAGUAUCAUUUGGUACUUUUUUUGUAAAUUGCUUUGUUUUGUUUAAUCAGAUACUGUGGAAUAAAAGCACCUUUUGCUUUUCUCACUAACCACACACUCUUGCAGAGCUUUCAGGUGUUACUCAGCUGCAUAGUUACGCAGAUGUAAUGCACAUUAUUGGCGUAUCUUUAAGUUGGAUUCAAAUGGCCAUUUUUCUCCAAUUUUGGUAAAUUGGAUAUCUUUUUUUUACAAAUACGACCAUUAACCUCAGUUAAAUUUUUGUUUGUUUUCCUGUUUGAUGCUGUCUAUUUGCAUUGAGUGUAAGUCAUUUGAACUAAUGGUAUAACUCCUAAAGCUUUCUCUGCUCCAGUUAUUUUUAUUAAAUAUUUUUCACUUGGCUUAUUUUUAAAACUGGGAACAUAAAGUGCCUGUAUCUUGUAAAACUUCAUUUGUUUCUUUUGGUUCAGAGAAGUUCAUUUAUGUUCAAAGACGUUUAUUCAUGUUCAACAGGAAAGACAAAGUGUACGUGAAUGCUCGCUGUCUGAUAGGGUUCCAGCUCCAUAUAUAUAGAAAGAUCGGGGGUGGGAUGGGAUGGAGUGAGCCCCAUCCAGUUAGUUGGACUAGUUUUAAAUAAAGGUUUUCCGGUUUGUGUUUUUUUGAACCAUACUGUUUAGUAAAAUAAAUACAAUGAAUGUUGAGUACUAGUGUCUGUUAUGUGUCUUCUUUAGAGGUGACACUCACAUGAAACAAUUUUUUCUUCUCAUAGGAAGCAGUAGCUUUAAACUGUCUGUGGUUCAUUAUUCUCAAUAUGAAUCAUACCAAGAUAUUUGUGCCUCAUCUCGAAAAUAUAUUGUAUAUUG